GCCACUUCCUAAUUAGUGGUUAAGGAGACACAUUUUUACUUGGGUGGUGGCUUUUUGUUUUGUUUUUAGGUUUUACAUUGAGGGGGGGAUUAAUAUUUAUUGAAUAUCUACUAGUUGUUAAGUACUUUAAAAAAUAUAUUAGCUGGGCGUGGUGGCACAUGCUUGUAGUUCCAGCUACUCAGGAAGCUGAGGCUGGAGGAUCCCUUGAGCCCAGGAAUUCGAGUCCAGCUUGGGCAACAUAACAAAACCCUGUCUCUAAAAAAUAGAUAUAUAUUUCUUCAUGUAAUUCUUACAUAGCCCUGUGAAAUACAGUCACGUGCCGUAUAACAGCAUUUUGGUCAGUGAGGGACCACACUGUUACAUGAUGGUAGUCCCAUAAGAUUAUAAUGCUGUAUUUUUACUUCACCUUUUCUAUGUUAGAUACAGAUGAUUCUUGUGUUACAGUUGCCUACAGUAUUCAGUACAGUUACAUACUGUACAGGUUUCUAGCCUAGGAGCAAGAGGCUACACCACUUAGACUAUGCCAUCUAAGUUUGUGUAAGUACACGCUGUGAGGUUCACACAGCAACAAAAUUGCCUAACGCUGCACAUUAACAGCCCCACUUUACAGAUUAGGAAACGGGUGCGAGAAGGUUAAUACCUUGCUCAAGGUCAUGUGGUUAAUAUUAAAGCUGGCAUUUGAGCCUUUCUGACCUGUCCUGCUAUGAUCCCCACUGUGGCUACUAGUGAUGGUAAUUCUGACCUUUUCAGGGGUAUGGGCAGCGGUGGUAGUUAUCUUUAAAAUAUAUCUUUUUCAGACUUCUCACUCUGUAAAAUAUGUAAUUAGACAUAGAUAUGUGUAGAGUGGCCUUUCUCAGAGGACCCGCAGCUCUUAGCAGUUGCUUGGCUAAUCUUCAUACCAUCUCUGUAAGAUAAACGGUGUUUUCUGGUUGGGUAGUUGAGGCCCAGAUAGGCUCAGGGACUCACCCAGCGCCUUAUCACAAACCCACACGGCCCAGCCCCCAGUUCCGUUCUUCGUCCUGUCUAGCAUAGAUUUCACCACUUUUGUUCUUUCCUGUCUUACACCAAGAUUGUUUAAGUACUUCCCAAAAAUAAUGAGCCACGUGUGGGUGUGUUCGUUCUCCAGAAUGAAUCACUGUGAAAGAGGUUGUGAACUAACGAAAUAAGCAUAAGUAUCUGGAAGCAGAGGCUCCUGACUAUUCAGUCCCUCUAAUUGGUGGGCUCUGGAGUGAGCGCUUUUCUGAAAGGCAACUGUGGGUUUGGGCUUGUGUCUCACUGUGCUCAGAAUAGUCCUCUCUUGAAGUUGUUACUUUUCCCUUCUUGCUUCCCAAAAUAGAACCAAUGUUGUUCUCUUUGCUGGACAUCACAACACAAAUAUUGAGAGGUAUGCUUUCCAUAGAGAACCCCUUUUAAAGUGCCUGAAUGUCCCCACUGCCACAAAGGGGAAUGGGAGUUAGCUUUCUUAAGAUUCCAGUGUGAGUAAAAGAGCUUUGGAUCAAGUAUUCUGUGAGUUUCAGAAGUAAAUGUAAAAGCAGAAAGAAUAAGAGAGGGAGCAAACAAAGGUAUUUGGAAGGGAAAAUGAAGCGAUUCCUUAGUCUUUUUUGUGUCUAAAUGGGUUAGAAUAAAAAUUCAGGAGAAAUUUACUUUUAAAAAUCCCUUUUAUGAUUUGGAUCCUAGUCUAAUAGGCACCUACUUUAAAUGUUCUGCCUUUAAGAAAUAACACUACCCAAACUCUGAAGCAAGAGGCUGCAUGUUUUGGAAUUUCUCCCAGAAGAAAGGGAUCUGAUGAAACGUGAAAAAAUACAACAGGCCAUAAGUGAAGAUCUGCACUGUCUACACUGUCUAUCCACCUGCCAGGGCUGCCUCCUUGGUUUCCUCGGGUGGGACUAGCAAGGAAUCGGCUCAUUUAUAGAAAGCCUAAGGAAGGAGGGGUUGGGCACUGAGAUAUUUAGAAUCUGUCUUUGGAUUUGAAAAGCCAAGAGAUGCCUUUCAGAAUAUUGGAGGAAGAGACGAAGAUAGACUGUGUACAGCCUAAAUUGCUCUGCUGUGUGCGUGCACCAGCUGCCUCCAGGCCAACUACACGUGUGAGACAGAUGGGGCCUGCAUGGUUUCCAUUUUCAAUCUGGAUGGGAUGGAGCACCAUGUGCGCACCUGCAUCCCCAAAGUGGAGCUGGUCCCUGCCGGGAAGCCCUUCUACUGCCUGAGCUCGGAGGACCUGCGCAACACCCACUGCUGCUACACUGACUACUGCAACAGGAUCGACUUGAGGGUGCCCAGUGGUCACCUCAAGGAGCCUGAGCACCCGUCCAUGUGGGGCCCGGUGGAGCUGGUAGGCAUCAUCGCCGGCCCGGUGUUCCUCCUGUUCCUCAUCAUCAUCAUUGUUUUCCUUGUCAUUAACUAUCAUCAGCGUGUCUAUCACAACCGCCAGAGACUGGACAUGGAAGAUCCCUCAUGUGAGAUGUGUCUCUCCAAAGACAAGACGCUCCAGGAUCUUGUCUACGAUCUCUCCACCUCAGGGUCUGGCUCAGGGUUACCCCUCUUUGUCCAGCGCACAGUGGCCCGAACCAUCGUUUUACAAGAGAUUAUUGGCAAGGGUCGGUUUGGGGAAGUAUGGCGGGGCCGCUGGAGGGGUGGUGAUGUGGCUGUGAAAAUAUUCUCUUCUCGUGAAGAACGGUCUUGGUUCAGGGAAGCAGAGAUAUACCAGACGGUCAUGCUGCGCCAUGAAAACAUCCUUGGAUUUAUUGCUGCUGACAAUAAAGCAGACUGCUCAUUCCUCACAUUGCCAUGGGAAGUUGUAAUGGUCUCUGCUGCCCCCAAGCUGAGGAGCCUUAGACUCCAAUACAAGGGAGGAAGGGGAAGAGCAAGAUUUUUAUUCCCACUGAAUAAUGGCACCUGGACACAGCUGUGGCUUGUUUCUGACUAUCAUGAGCACGGGUCCCUGUUUGAUUAUCUGAACCGGUACACAGUGACAAUUGAGGGGAUGAUUAAGCUGGCCUUGUCUGCUGCUAGUGGGCUGGCACACCUGCACAUGGAGAUCGUGGGCACCCAAGGGAAGCCUGGAAUUGCUCAUCGAGACUUAAAGUCAAAGAACAUUCUGGUGAAGAAAAAUGGCAUGUGUGCCAUAGCAGACCUGGGCCUGGCUGUCCGUCAUGAUGCAGUCACUGACACCAUUGACAUUGCCCCGAAUCAGAGGGUGGGGACCAAACGAUACAUGGCCCCUGAAGUACUUGAUGAAACCAUUAAUAUGAAACACUUUGACUCCUUUAAAUGUGCUGAUAUUUAUGCCCUCGGGCUUGUAUAUUGGGAGAUUGCUCGAAGAUGCAAUUCUGGAGGAGUCCAUGAAGAAUAUCAGCUGCCAUAUUACGACUUAGUGCCCUCUGACCCUUCCAUUGAGGAAAUGCGAAAGGUUGUAUGUGAUCAGAAGCUGCGUCCCAACAUCCCCAACUGGUGGCAGAGUUAUGAGGCACUGCGGGUGAUGGGGAAGAUGAUGCGAGAGUGUUGGUAUGCCAACGGCGCAGCCCGCCUGACGGCCCUGCGCAUCAAGAAGACCCUCUCCCAGCUCAGCGUGCAGGAAGACGUGAAGAUCUAACUGCUCCCUCUCUCCACACGGAGCUCCUGGCAGCGAGAACUACGCACAGCUGCCGCGUUGAGCGUACGAUGGAGGCCUACCUCUCGUUUCUGCCCAGCCCUCUGUGGCCAGGAGCCCUGGCCCGCAAGAGGGACAGAGCCCGGGAGAGACUCGCUCACUCCCAUGUUGGGUUUGAGACAGACACCUUUUCUAUUUACCUCCUAAUGGCAUGGAGACUCUGAGAGCGAAUUGUGUGGAGAACUCAGUGCCACACCUCGAACUGGUUGUAGUGGGAAGUCCCGCGAAACCCGGUGCAUCUGGCACGUGGCCAGGAGCCAUGACAGGGGCGCUUGGGAGGGGCCGGAGGAACCGAGGUGUUGCCAGUGCUAAGCUGCCCUGAGGGUUUCCUUCGGGGACCAGCCCACAGCACACCAAGGUGGCCCGGAAGAACCAGAAGUGCAGCCCCUCUCACAGGCAGCUCUGAGCCGCGCUUUCCCCUCCUCCCUGGGAUGGACGCUGCCGGGAGACUGCCAGUGGAGACGGAAUCUGCCGCUUUGUCUGUCCAGCCGUGUGUGCAUGUGCCGAGGUGCGUCCCCCGUUGUGCCUGGUUCGUGCCAUGCCCUUACACGUGCGUGUGAGUGUGUGUGUGUGUCUGUAGGUGCGCACUUACCUGCUUGAGCUUUCUGUGCAUGUGCAGGUCGGGGGUGUGGUCGUCAUGCUGUCCGUGCUUGCUGGUGCCUCUUUUCAGUAGUGAGCAGCAUCUAGUUUCCCUGGUGCCCUUCCCUGGAGGUCUCUCCCUCCCCCAGAGCCCCUCAUGCCACAGUGGUACUCUGUGUCUGGCAGGCUACUCUGCCCACCCCAGCAUCAGCACAGCUCUCCUCCUCCAUCUCAGACUGUGGAACCAAAGCUGGCCCAGUUGUCCAUGACAAAAGAGGCUUUUGGGCCAAAAUGUGAGGGUGGUGGGUGGGAUGGGCAGGGAAGGAAUCCUGGUGGAAGUCUUGGGUGUUAGUGUCAGCCAUGGGAAAUGAGCCAGCCCAAGGGCAUCAUCCUCAGCAGCAUCGAGGAAGGGCCGAGGAAUGUGAAGCCAGAUCUCGGGACUCAGAUUGGAAUGUUACAUCUGUCUUUCAUCUCCCAGAUCCUGGAAACAGCAGUGUAUAUUUUUGGUGGUGGUGGGUUUGGGGUGGGGAAGGGAAGGGCGGGCAAGGAGUGGGGAGGGAGUCUGGGGUGGGAGGGAGGCAUCUGCAUGGGUCUUCUUUUACUGGACUGUCUGAUCAGGGUGGAGGGAAGGUGAGAGGUUUGCAUCCACUUCAGGAGCCCUACUGAAGGGAACAGCCUGAGCCGAACAUGUUAUUUAACCUGAGUAUAGUAUUUAACGAAGCCUAGAAGCACGGCUGUGGGUGGUGAUUUGGUCAGCAUAUCUUAGGUAUAUAAUAACUUUGAAGCCAUAACUUUUAACUGGAGUGGUUUGAUUUCUUUUUUUAAUUUUAUUGGGAGGGUUUGGAUUUUAACUUUUUUUAAUGUUGUUAAAUAUUAAGUUUUUGUAAAAGGAAAACCAUCUCUGUGAUUACCUCUCAAUCUAUUUGUUUUUAAAGAAAUCCCUAAAAAAAAAAAUUAUCCAAUUGAACGCACAUAGCUCAAUCACACUGGAAAUGUUUGUCCUUGCACCUGAGCCUGUUCCCACUCAGCAGUGAGAGUUCCUCUUUGCCCUGAGGCUCAGUCUCUCUCGUAUUUUGUCCCCACCCCCAAUUCCUUGAGUGGUUUUUGCUCUAGGGCCCUUUCUUGCACUGUCCAGCUGGUUGUACCCUCUCCAGGCAUUUAUUCAACAAAUGUGGGUGAAGUGCCUGCUGGGUGCCAGGUGCUGGGAAUACAUCUGUGGACAAGACAUGCUUGGGUCCUACUCCUGGAGCACUGUAAAAAGAGCUGAUUCAAGUAAGUAGAUGCCUGUUUUGAGACCAGAAGGUUUCAUAAUUGGUUCUACGACCCUUUUGAGCCUAGAAUUAUUGUUCUUAUAUAAGAUCACUGAAGAAAGAGGAACCCCCACAACCCCCUCCACAAAGAGACCAGGGGCGGGUGAUGAGACCUGGGGUUUAGAACCCCAGGUGAGACCUCAAAUCACUGCAUUCAUUCUGAGCCCCCUUCCUGUCCCCAGGGGAGGUGUAUUGUGUAUGUAGCCUUAGAGCAUCUCUGCCUCCAACCCAGCAGUUCUCUGCCAAAGCUUGUGGAGGAGGGAGAGCCCUGUCCCUGCCCUCAGGCUCCCCAGUGCUCCUGGCCCUUCUAUUUAUUUGACUGAUUAUUGCUUCUUUCCUUGCAUUAAAGGAGAUCUUCCCCUAACCUUUGGGCCAAUUUACUGGCCACUAAUUUCGUUUAAAUACCAUUGUGUCAUUGGGGGGACCGUCUUUACCCCUGCUGACCUCCCACCUAUCCGCCCUGCAGCAGAACCUUGGCGGUUUAUAGGUAAUGAUGGAACUUAGACUCCUCUUCCCAGAGUCACAAGUAGCCUCUGGGAUCUGCCAACACACGUCCACUCCCAAGCCACUAGCCCACUCCCCAGUUGGCCCUUCUGCCCUUACCCCACACACAGUCCAACUCUUCCACCUCUGGGGAAGAUGGAGCAGGUCUUUGGGAAGCUCCCACACCCACCUCUGCCACUCUUAACACUAAGUGAGAGUUGGGGAGAAACUGAAGCCGUGUUUUUGGCCCCCCGAGGCUAACCCUGAUCCAUAGUGCUACCUGCACCUCUGGAUUCUGGAUUCACAGACCAAGUCCAAGCCCGUUCUUACGUCGCCAUAAAGGCCCCCGAACGGCAUUCUCGGUACUUCUGUUUGUUUUUGUACAUUUUAUUAGAAAGGACUGUAAAAUAGCCACUUAGACACUUUACCUCUUCAGUAUGCAAAUGUAAAUAAAUUGUAAUAUAGGAAAUCUUUUGUUUUAAUAUAAGAAUGAGCCUGUCCAAUUUCUGCUGUACAUUAUUAAAAGUUUUAUUCACAGA